GGGCGGCGCCCAGGAGGCGCCCGGGUGAGGCACGGGUGCGCAAGCGGGAGUUCCGGCUGGAGACCCGUGCUCUGGGCCGGCGCCUUCACCAUGGCCUCGGCAGAGCUGGACUACACCAUCGAGAUCCCGGAUCAGCCCUGCUGGAGCCAGAAGAACAGCCCCAGCCCAGGUGGGAAGGAGGCAGAAACUCGGCAGCCUGUGGUGAUUCUCUUGGGCUGGGGUGGCUGCAAGGACAAGAACCUUGCCAAGUACAGUGCCAUCUACCACAAAAGGGGCUGCAUCGUAAUCCGAUACACAGCCCCGUGGCACAUGGUCUUCUUCUCCGAGUCACUGGGUAUCCCUUCACUUCGUGUUUUGGCCCAGAAGCUGCUCGAGCUGCUCUUUGAUUAUGAGAUUGAGAAGGAGCCCCUGCUCUUCCAUGUCUUCAGCAACGGUGGCGUCAUGCUGUACCGCUACGUGCUGGAGCUCCUGCAGACCCGUCGCUUCUGCCGCCUGCGUGUGGUGGGCACCAUCUUUGACAGCGCUCCUGGUGACAGCAACCUGGUAGGGGCUCUGCGGGCCCUGGCAGCCAUCCUGGAGCGCCGGGCCGCCAUGCUGCGCCUGUUGCUGCUGGUGGCCUUUGCCCUGGUGGUCGUCCUGUUCCACGUCCUGCUUGCUCCCAUCACAGCCCUCUUCCACACCCACUUCUAUGACAGGCUACAGGACGCGGGCUCUCGCUGGCCCGAGCUCUACCUCUACUCGAGGGCUGACGAAGUAGUCCUGGCCAGAGACAUAGAACGCAUGGUGGAGGCACGCCUGGCACGCCGGGUCCUGGCGCGUUCUGUGGAUUUCGUGUCAUCUGCACACGUCAGCCACCUCCGUGACUACCCUACUUACUACACAAGCCUCUGUGUCGACUUCAUGCGCAACUGCGUCCGCUGCUGAGGCCAUUGCUCCAUCUCACCUCUGCUCCAGAAAUAAAUGCCUGACACCUCCCCACAACCUGCAAUCUGUCGGGCACUCUUCUCGUUCAACUCCCUGUAGCCCUUUGGGACUUUGCGGUCCCCUAAGUAGAAAAUUCCUAUGGGCCUGUCUCCUGGGGGCCUCUGUCUGCUGGUGGUCUGCUUACCACAGAAUCCUAAGGGGCAGGAGUGCCUGGGCAUGUGUCUGUGGGAGCCUUGCAGUCAGUUGUGUUUGGACAAGUGCAACAGUCAGGCUGCUGAUUCCUGUGGCAUGCAGGCUGUAGAGGUUGACAAAUGGAGGGGGGUGUUGAGGGUGAGCCCUAGUUGAUUUUUUAAAAUUUAAACUCUGGUAAGAACAUUUAAUAUGAGACCUACUCUCUUUUUUUCUUUACUUAUUUAUUUAUCUAUUUAUUUCAAGACAGGGUCUCACUCUGUCACCUAGGCUGGGGUGCAAUGGUGCAAUCAUGGCUCACUGCAGCCUCAACCUCCCAGGCUCAAGUGAUCCUCCCACCUCAGCCUCCCAAAGUGCUAGGAUUACAGGCAUGAGUCACCGCGCCUGGCCAAGAUCACCUAACAAAAUUGUAAGUGUGUACGAUACUUAAAAUUUAAGAGAUUAUGUGCACGGCAGACCUCUAGAACUGAAUAGUCUUGCAUCUUGCAUAAUUCAGAACUUCAUCAUCUUGCAUAACUGAAACUUUGUGCCUGUUACCAGAGUUGAGUUUUGAUUCCUUGAAUGGAAGGUGACCUUUGUGGGGAGAUGCCAGAGGGAAGGUAUAUCGGUCAGGGGUAGCGUCAGGCUGCGGAUAGGGGCUAUGAUCUUUGCUCCAGCAGGGCGAAGCCCUACAGUGUAAAGUACCAUUCACAUGGCUCCCACUUGGCAGUUCACUCAGAGAGGCUCCUCUGACCCCAUUGCCUGGGAGUCUGAGGUAGAAGCCAGAUGAGGAGCUGAGGUUAGGGGCCUGCCUGGCUCUACCACACUUUGCUAGGAAGCCGCUGGGUCUGGGAAAGUUGCAAGCUGAAAGUUGCCAGAGACAGUGGGGGGCAGGAAGGCAGCAGCAUUGUAACAGGAGCUGGGAUGAGCUAACUCCCAAGCCCUAAAGACCAGAACCAGGGUAAGGGGAUUUGGGCUGAAAUAGCAAACUCCUUCAUCUUCUGGAAGGGAGACCCACUUAGAUACUCUCUAGGCAGAAGAGGUGAAUUCAGCCUGAUAGUUCAGUAUCAUUGAUCAUUCUAGAAGUCACUACUGCACAAUGUUGGCAUAUAGUAGGUAUUCAAUAAAUAUUUGAUUGAAUGAG